GGAAACGCGGAGCGCGCGCUCCCAGCGAAAGCAGCAGGGCAGGGAUCUGCGUUGGAGGAAGGGACUGCUCUGGUGCUAGAAUGCUGUGCGUCGGAAGGCUGGGCGGCUUGGGAGCCAGAGCAGCAGCUCUGCCGCCCCGCCGGGCGGGCCGGGGAAGCCUCGAAGCCGGGAUCCGGGCCCGAAGGGUCAGCACCAGCUGGUCUCCCGUGGGCGCCGCCUUCAAUGUCAAGCCCCAGGGCAGCCGCUUGGACCUGUUCGGCGAGCGCCGGGUGAGCGGCGCAGGAGGAGCUCCCCUCAGUCCCCGAGCUAAGCCGACCCCUGCUCCGCGCGGCCAGCAACAAUCAGGGCGAGAUUGUUUGGGCCUGGGAGGAGGCGAGCAGCGAACCCACCUUUUACAGUGGCGUCUUGUGUGCGCUCUCGAUGAGGGCAAGGUCACCUCUGCUUUGAGGGGCCGGGUUUAGUGGUCUCCUACCCAGAGUGUCGGGUCCGGGAACUGCUUCUGCAUGAGCCCCUUGCUCCACGUGAAUCUGAAUAGUUCGUUCUGGCAGUGGCGGUGAAUUCGUCCUGCCAGGACCCGCCCUCUGCAUACACUCAGGCGCACCCCUGCUAAAGCCCUUUAGCUCCAGCGCUACAGUCCUGCCUUAAGAGGCCUAUCCCUGUGCGUUCACAGGCGGCAUCACAUGGUCUUUUUGCAAGGACACGGCUGCCUGCAGUCGAGUAAUGGGUCUUUUUGGAGUUCCUGAGCUGAGUGCCCCAGAAGGAUUUCAUAUUGCACAAGAAAAAGCCUUGAGAAAGACAGAAUUGCUUGUGGACCGUGCAUGUUCCACCCCACCUGGGCCCCAGACCGUGCUGAUCUUCGAUGAGCUCUCGGAUUCCUUAUGCAGAGUGGCCGACUUGGCUGAUUUUGUGAAAAUCGCUCACCCUGAGCCAGCAUUCAGAGAAGCUGCGGAAGAAGCUUGUAGAAGUAUUGGCACCAUGGUAGAGAAGUUGAACACAAAUGUGGAUUUAUAUCAAAGUUUGCAAAAAUUACUAGCUGAUAAAAAACUUGUGGAUUCCCUUGAUCCAGAAACAAGGCGAGUGGCUGAACUGUUUAUGUUUGAUUUUGAAAUUAGUGGAAUCCAUCUAGACAAAGAAAAGCGUAAAAGAGCAGUGGACCUCAAUGUUAAAAUCUUGGAUUUGAGUAGUACAUUUCUUAUGGGAACCAAUUUUCCCAACAAGAUUGAGAAGCAUCUCUUACCAGAACACAUUCGUCGUAACUUUACAUCUGCUGGGGAUCAUAUCAUAAUUGAUGGUCUCCACGCAGAAUCACCAGAUGACUUGGUGCGAGAAGCUGCUUAUAAAAUUUUUCUUUAUCCCAAUGCUGGUCAAUUGAAAUGUUUAGAAGAAUUGCUCAGCAGCAGAGAUCUUCUGGCAAAGUUGGUGGGGUAUUCCACGUUUUCUCACAGGGCUCUCCAAGGAACGAUAGCUAAAAAUCCAGAGACUGUCAUGCAGUUCCUUGAAAAACUAUCUGACAAACUUUCUGAAAGAACUCUGAAAGAUUUUGAGAUGAUACGAGGGAUGAAAAUGAAACUGAAUCCUCAAAAUUCCGAAGUAAUGCCCUGGGACCCCCCUUACUACAGUGGUGUGAUUCGUGCAGAAAGGUAUAAUAUUGAGCCCAGCCUAUAUUGCCCGUUUUUCUCUCUUGGAGCAUGCAUGGAAGGCCUGAAUAUUUUGCUUAACAGACUGUUGGGGAUUUCAUUAUAUGCAGAGCAGCCUGCAAAAGGAGAGGUGUGGAGCGAAGAUGUCCGAAAACUGGCUGUUGUUCAUGAAUCUGAAGGAUUGUUGGGGUACAUUUACUGUGAUUUUUUUCAGCGAGCAGACAAACCACAUCAGGAUUGCCAUUUCACUAUCCGUGGAGGCAGACUAAAGGAAGAUGGAGACUAUCAACUCCCAGUUGUAGUUCUUAUGCUGAAUCUUCCCCGUUCCUCAAGGAGUUCUCCAACUUUGCUAACUCCUAGCAUGAUGGAAAAUCUUUUCCAUGAAAUGGGACAUGCCAUGCAUUCAAUGCUAGGACGUACUCGUUACCAACACGUCACUGGGACCAGGUGCCCUACUGAUUUUGCUGAGGUUCCUUCUAUUCUGAUGGAGUACUUUGCAAAUGAUUAUCGAGUAGUUAACCAAUUUGCCAGACAUUAUCAGACUGGACAGCCACUGCCAAAAAAUAUGGUGUCUCGUCUUUGUGAAUCUAAAAAGGUUUGUGCUGCAGCUGAUAUGCAACUUCAGGUCUUUUAUGCCACUCUGGAUCAAAUCUACCAUGGGAAGCAUCCCCUGAGGAAUUCAACCACAGACAUUCUCAAGGAAACACAAGAGAAAUUCUAUGGCCUACCAUAUGUUCCAAAUACUGCUGUACAGGAAGCAUAACACUGGCAUCUGCUCAGCUUCUGGGAAGGCCUCAGGAAGUUUACACUCAUGGCAGAAGGCAAAGGGGGAGAGUGGUGUCUUACAUGAUGGCAGCAGGAGCAAGAGAGAGAGAGGGUAGGUGCCACAUACUUUUAAACAACCCGAUCUUACAAGAAAUCACUAUUGUGUCAACAGCACCAACGGGGAUAGUGUUAAACCAUGAGAAUCCACCCCAAUGAUCCAAUCCCCUCCUACCAGGCCCUAUCUCCAAUGUUGUGGAUUACAAUUUGACAUGAGAUUUGGGCCAAGACACAUAUCUAGACUAUAUCGGGGGAUUUAUAUAAUCUAUAAACAUUGGUUACCUGUCCAUCUUUUUGAGUAGGUGUGUGCUGCAGACUUAUUGGGGACAUAAUCAGAUAUACCUGAUUUGCUGCAGUAUACUCAAGGUGUAUUAGUUGAGAAAGGUUGCUGCUACUGGAGACUGGUUUCUAUUCAGACUAAUUUCUAUUAAGUCUAAUUAUGUAGAAGUGAUAUAUAUUUCAUAUUAAGUAUAAUUUUCUAUGUGUAACAAACUGUUUUUAGAAAAAAACUGCCAAAAAUUGUGCUGAAUUUAGUCAGACACUCCAAAGAGCAAACACACUUUUGUUUUUUAGCAUAAAGAAAACUAUUUCAAAUCCCAAUUAAAAUAGUUGUACAAUAAUUUGCUUUUUGUAUUUAUAUUGUGAUAACUACAAAUUUUUAAUAAUUGAUAUAAUGUAUAUGUAUGUGUUAUCUUUUUAUUAAGUGCCUACUACGUGCUACCACAUGGUCUAAGCAAUGGAUGUAACAGUAAAUAAAGUAGACCAGAAUCCUUGCUCUCAUGGA